ACCAUCCCCUUGGGACUUUUGAGUGACACAAACAUUCGAACCAUUUGGCCCCUGAUGAAAUUCCUAACCUCCCCUUGUUAGAGUCAGUCUCCUCCCGGCUCUCCACUGCCACUGUCUCUGGCUGCCACCUUGGUCCUAAAGCAGCCUGGCCCUACUGGCUCGCUGCUCUCAUUCUCUGGAGCCAGACUUCUGAUUCCCAUGCAUUUGACCUCUGGCCUCCUCAGCCCACACCACCUCAACUCUUGAGCAUGGAGCCCAGGAGGAGGUCCCUCCGGGGACAAGGUCACCACCCCUCUGCGCCUCCCUCUAAGUGGGGUCAGCCCGAGGCCAAGCUGAGAACCUGCCCCAGCCUCCCUGCAGGCCUGGCCUGGGACCCUCCUGUGGAGGAGCUGGGUGCCCAGGGAGACCCUCGCAGGCAGCCAGACAGCCUGAAGAGAACAGGGUCACUCUGGGAUAACCUAAGUCACUCUACAGCCUCACCAAAGAGAUGGGGGCACCCUCUCCUGCGUGGGAGGAGCCCACAGAAACCUGAGGCUGGAGGGAUUCCCUGGUGGGAAAGGCACGCAGGGCUUCGGGGAGACUUGCUGAAGUCUCCAGGGGAAGCCCUGAGCCAGAGCUGGGGUCAGGACUCGCUGGAGCCAGCACCAGCUCCGUGUACAGUAAGAGCUCAGAGAGCAACUGAAUUUGGGUGGCUGGAAAACCGAGUGGUCAGGCCACUGCCAGCCUCAUUUUCCCCCAGAAGCAGACCCCGGGAGGCUUUCACCCACAGCCACCCUCAGAGCAGCCAGCCCACUCCCGGAAGAGCUGGACGCUGGAUCAGCACGCUCCCCUCCAACACUCCCUGGGGAACAGAGGCCAACACAUGGGCUGGAGCACCGUGCUGUGAUGCCACAAUUCAAGGGCCUAUCUUUGUACGCAGCUGAAAAGAGGAAAUUCAGCGCCAGCGUAGCUUCUCAGCGGCAGCUCACCCCAAGCUGCCAAGGAGGAUGUGGGCAGGCAGUGGGCAGCUGUGUUUCGGGAGGCCUGCAACGCUCCACUUCCCUAGCGCGCUCACAUGGGAUCCCUGGGUUUCCAGACUCAUAAUGUGCACGGAGGGACGGCUGGCUGAGAAGUUUUGAAAUCCAUCCCUCGUCGAUGGGGUCUUAUGCCAGUUCUACUUAAUACUUUGUUUUUCUAAUUCUAAGCAUCAGUUCUCUGCCAGAAAAUGAGUUGCGUUUGCUUCAAAAACACUACAAAACGCAGAACUGGCAAGUAUAAAUGGCUCUAAAUUUAAUAAAUAUUGAUCACCCAA